AGUGCUCCCCGGCUUCCGCGGCGGCCGGGCGCCUGGGGCGGGAGAGGAGCCUCUGCGGAGCCUGGGCGCGGCCGGACCCCGGUUCGCGGGGCGCGGCGCCAGCGUCGGGACGGUGGGAGAGUUCUUGAACGACUUCCCGGUCUUUGCCAAAAGUUACAUCCACAGCGGUGUUUGUGGGUCUCUUACGGCUAUAACGGAGUUGAAGGCGCAGUGCGGACUGAUUGAAUAGCGGUCAUCUUUUGCAGCCGUGAGCACUUCCGAGCCUCCCUGCCGCCGGGAGAAAGCCCGGCUCCCCUGGCUUUUCAAAAGCUCUCCCGUUUUAUCCGAUGGUGUGGUCGUCCAAGUUUUCCUCCAUUGGGAUUUUAAACCGUUUUUUUCCCGCCUUGACUCUUUUGUACUCUAAAAGAACGCGUUUGUUCACUGUUUUGAACCUUUCCAGUUACUUUUGUAGAUUUAUCUCGCUUGUUAGUAAGCCAGCGGUUUUCCAAGUGUGGUUACAACUAUUUUCGUUAAUAGUACCAAGGUCGUGUACAUCGAGUUUUCCAAAGGCUACAUGCUCUUUCAGUCUCACAUGGCAACGAAAACAACUUGUAUGUCUUCACAAGGAUCAGAUGAUGAACAGAUAAAAAGAGAAAACAUUCGUUCGUUGACUAUGUCUGGCCAUGUUGGUUUUGAGAGUUUGCCUGAUCAGCUGGUGAACAGAUCCAUUCAGCAAGGUUUCUGCUUUAAUAUUCUCUGUGUGGGGGAAACUGGAAUUGGAAAAUCAACACUGAUUGACACAUUGUUUAAUACUAAUUUUGAAGACUAUGAAUCCUCACAUUUUUGCCCAAAUGUUAAACUUAAAGCUCAGACAUAUGAACUCCAGGAAAGUAAUGUUCAAUUGAAAUUGACCAUUGUGAAUACAGUGGGAUUUGGUGACCAAAUAAAUAAAGAAGAGAGCUACCAACCAAUAGUUGACUACAUAGAUGCUCAGUUUGAGGCCUAUCUCCAAGAAGAACUGAAGAUUAAGCGUUCUCUCUUUACCUACCAUGAUUCUCGCAUCCAUGUGUGUCUCUACUUCAUUUCACCGACAGGCCACUCUCUGAAGACACUUGAUCUCUUAACCAUGAAGAACCUUGACAGCAAGGUAAACAUUAUACCAGUGAUUGCCAAAGCAGAUACGGUUUCUAAAACUGAAUUACAGAAGUUUAAGAUCAAGCUCAUGAGUGAAUUGGUCAGCAAUGGCGUCCAGAUAUACCAGUUCCCAACGGAUGAUGACACUAUUGCUAAGGUCAACGCUGCAAUGAAUGGACAGUUGCCGUUUGCUGUUGUGGGAAGUAUGGAUGAGGUAAAAGUCGGAAACAAGAUGGUCAAAGCUCGCCAGUACCCUUGGGGUGUUGUACAAGUGGAAAAUGAAAACCACUGUGACUUUGUAAAGCUGCGGGAAAUGCUCAUUUGUACAAAUAUGGAGGACCUGCGAGAGCAGACCCAUACCAGGCACUAUGAGCUUUACAGGCGCUGCAAACUGGAGGAAAUGGGCUUUACAGAUGUGGGCCCAGAAAACAAGCCAGUCAGUGUUCAAGAGACCUAUGAAGCCAAAAGACAUGAGUUCCAUGGUGAACGUCAGAGGAAGGAAGAAGAAAUGAAACAGAUGUUUGUGCAGCGAGUAAAGGAGAAAGAAGCCAUAUUGAAAGAAGCUGAGAGAGAGCUACAGGCCAAAUUUGAGCACCUUAAGAGACUUCACCAAGAAGAGAGAAUGAAGCUUGAAGAAAAGAGAAGACUUUUGGAAGAAGAAAUAAUUGCUUUCUCUAAAAAGAAAGCUACCUCCGAGAUAUUUCACAGCCAGUCCUUUCUGGCAACAGGCAGCAACCUGAGGAAGGACAAGGACCGUAAGAAGUAAGAGGCCCAGCCACCCUCCCUGGCAGCCCUGCCCACACUUGUCACAUUGCCCUGUCGGAUCUUCCUAGCGCUUCUUACUUCUGCUUCCUUAUGCUUUGUCUUCCUUCUCCAACUAAAUGUCAGCUCCUGGAGAGGAGAGACCUUGUCCCUCUUGUUCACUGCUGUUUCCCCAGCAUCCAGAACAGCACCUGGCACAUGUUAUGUGUUCAGUAUUUGCCAAAAUGAAUGAAUGAACAAAAUAAAAAUACAUCACAGUGUGAAAAGGAUCAGUUAGCUGGGGGAAAAUGGCUGCUCUUAUUGAAUAGCCCAGCCGUGGCCCUAGUACACAGCUAAUGGCUGCUGACCUACCAUGAGUUAUUUUGAAUUUCAUGUCUAAAUAAAGCUGUGCCCUUUGUUGGGGAAUUAUAGACAUAAGAUAGUAUUUUAUUGAAUUAAUUCUUAGGUUCAGUUUUUUAGAACAAAUUCUACUGAUACUGAUUUUGUGAGAAUUUUUAUUUUAAUAAGGGAACCAGGCUGUCGAUUCGAACUCCUGUGCAUUGAUGUCAGAGCUUGUGAAACCAAUGGUGGACGUAAAGACGCAGAGAAAGGUAGAGAGGGCCACAGUGCAAGGGGGCAGCCAUGAGUAGCAUGUGGAUGAUAAUCGCAAGGCGUGUAGGUUUGGGGUAUGUGUUAAAAUCAGUUACCCAAGUUUUAGAAAAUAAGUUUAUUUUUCCUUUUUGAUAAUUUCCUUCUGUACUUUGUGUCCCUUGUUUUAUUUCUCCCACUUAAGUAUCCCUGUCGGUUUAACUAUUUGGCUCUUGAGGAAAUUCAUCAUGCCUUGUUCUAUUCAGAAUGCUCAUUUGGGGGACUCUGCCUCAGUUUACUCUAGCUACCUCUGUGCUAGCAGCGUUGCAUGCUCCCAUGUUCCCCACAGAGCAACACAUCUGGUUUAAUGCUCUCACUGCAUCUAUUUCAGACCCAUUUUCAGAAUAUUGCAACUCAACUUUAAAAUAGGAAAACAUAACCUUGGCCCAUUGGUGGCUUUCAAUUUUUAAAUAUGGAGAAGUAAACCACAGGACUUUGGCAGAUUUUAUUGGCUUAUAUAUUUUACAGGUAUUUUUGUUUGUUUGUUUGUUUUUUUGGAAAAGAGGAAGGAAUUCUCAUGUAUGAUCUUUCAAUGCAAGCUCUCCAAGGGCAUGGAUCUUUAUCUUGUUCAUUGAUAUAGCCAUCCCCAGAGCCUAGAGCAGUUGUCUGGUACAUAGUAGGCAUGCAAUUAUUUUUGAAAGAAUAAAUAGUAUAAAAGCUGUAUUUUAUUCAAGCAUUGAAUUUAGAAAGAUAAACUAUAAAUUUAUUACUGCUUUUCAACAUGCUUUGGAUUUUAAAGCUAAUGGAUCUUUUAUUAAUACCUUUUUUCCUUUCAUCUUAACCCAGUGUUACUAAAAUUAGAUUUCCCAUUUUUUCCCCUAUAUGAAAGAUAAUUUACAUUUACCUUGUAAAAAUUAUCACCCUGCUCCACUUGAGAACCCUGCUGUUGUUUGCAAAAUCAGGACCAAGCCCAUAUUUUUUGAGAGCUCUCUAGAAGAAUUUAUCUUCAAGAAAAUAUGGUUUGGUGUUUUUGGUUUUUUCUUUUCUUUUUCAAAGUCCCAUGGCCAGAUAUCCUAUAAUAUACUAGAUGCAUGUUUGCUAAUUUUUACUUGAAUUUUUUUUAAAUUGUACCAAUCAAAAGGUUCUUUUUCUUUCCAGCUCCAAUUUUUUGUAAAACAGAAGUUCCAGAGCACAGAAGGUCAUCAUCACAAGCAAACUUUAUUAAAAAAAAACUAGAAGUGUGCUUUGAUUUUGCUGUUAUUUGUUUUAUCACUUCUAUAUUUGGUGAACAGCCACAGUUACUGAUAUUUAUGGAAAAGUACUUUCAAGUACAAGGUCAAUACAUAAGCCAGAGUGAAUGAUACUACAAGUUGAGCAUCUCUAAUUCAAAAAUCUGAAAUCCAGAAGCUUCAAAAUCUGAAUCUUUUUGAGCACUGACUUGACCCCACAAGUGGAAAAUUCCCCACCCGACACCUUUGCUUUCUGAUGGUUCAGUUUAAACAGAUUUUGUUUCUUGCACAAAAUUUUUGUAUAAAUUACUUUCAGGCUAUAUGUAUAAGGUGGAUGUGAAACAUGAAUUAUGUAAUUAGAGUCGGGUCCCGUUGUGUAUAUGCAGAUAUUCCAAACCUGAAAUCCAAAACACUUCUGGUCCCUAGCAUUUUGGAUAAGGGAUACUCAGCUUGUACCUAUAUAUUCAUAUAUAUUCACUGUUGUUAGAAAUGUUUAAGUUGCUGUUCUGUGAUGAAUCUAAAUCUUUUCUCUUGCUACCAAGCUAUUGUCACUGCAGUGCAUUAUACCAAAGAGCGAAGUCAGUGCCACUGAAAAUACAGAACCCAUUAAUAUCGUGGCUAUCUGAUUACAUUUAUAUUCCAAGAUGAACCUUUUUUAUAUAUGCUAAAAAUUUUGGGGAAUAUGUUUUGGGAUGUAUUAUGGAGCUAAAACUCUAACCUCUUAAUAGUUUUAUAGAACUUAAAAAUUUUUUAUACAAUUACCCAAUUGGUGAUAUGAUCUUAAGCUUUUGUGUCAGAUUAUUUAAUAUGAUGACUUCAUGCUUUAUUAUGCCUUAUUAUGGCUGACGUAUUACUGUGGUGAAACAAAAUAUCUUUAAAAGUUAAAACAUCCAGAUAUAUAAGCUAUUUUUUCCUAAGGAUAAAGUACCUUUGAGCAUGAGUGUAUCACAGCUUUCAUUAGGAAAACUUUUCAUUACAUACUUGUUUAAACUCUGUCUUCCAGGGUAAAAAUAAUAAGGUUGAAUCAUUUUAUUAAAAAUACUUUUUAAGAAAAUAACUAUGAACAUCUGAAUAUUAAAGAUAUAAAAAUGCACAUAAUUCAUAUUUCAGGUGGUAUUUGCAUUCAGUGCCUUACUGGUAUUCUCAGAACAUUUUAAUGAUUUCUAACAUUUCUUAACAGUCAUAGAUAUAUACAUUUUCAUUUUUUGUACUUGAAUAUUCUAAAUAAAACUGACAUUUACUCUUGACAAAUAAAACAUAUAUUUACUAAAAUGUGUUUAAUUUUCCUUUCUGAAAACUCUCAUUUUAAAAACGUUCAUUUAAUUAUGUAUUUGAAUUAUUUUGGAGAUGAGGUAUUUUAUGAGUAUUUUCAGACAAUGAAACUUAUUAGUCUGUGUCAGAUUCUGAGCAAUCAUAGAGUCAUCUAAGUUGUAAAUAAAACCUUGCAUAGCACAA